GCGGGAGCGCGGAGCCGGCGCUGGGGACGGCGGCGCCGAGUCUGCGGGUCCUCCCGCCAGCCCGGCCGGAGGCAGCCGAGGCCGCUCGGGCGGCGGCGGCGGCGGCGGCGGGAGCCGGAGCGCAUCUCGCCCAGGAGCCGGAGCAGCGGCACUGCCUGAACCAGACAGCAGCCUUGGGUGCAGGCGUGGUCAUGAGGGCAGAUGGACACUGCUGAAGACCCGGCCUGGCUCCAGCUGCUUCAAAAGGAUUCCAGCCCCCCAGGACCCCGACCCACAGCCUUCUUCUGCCCACAGGAUGGGAGCCUGGGGGCUGGCAGCUCGGCUAUGAGGGAUUACUGCCCCUCCCAGCAAAAGGCAAGCCCUGCACCCCCCAGGCACACCCCUGACCAAAGCCCAGGCAUGGAGUCUAGACACAGAAGCCCCAGUGGGGCUGGGGAAGGGGCCUCCUGCUCUGACGGCCCCAGAGGGAGCCUGGCCUGCCCCUCCCCAACCUGCUUCUCUCCCCAGGAGUCACCCUCCAAGGAGACAUUGGAGGCACAUGGAGCCUCCAUCUCAGGGACACCAGAAGCCACCACGUCUGGGAAGCCAGAGCCUGUGUCCUCCGUGAAAACUGAGCCCAAAUCCUCAGAUGACAGAAAUCCCAUGUUCUUAGAGAAGAUGGAUUUCAAGUCCUCAAAGCAGGCCGAUUCCACUUCCAUAGGAAAGGAGGAUCCUGGGUCCUCACGGAAGGCAGAUCCCAUGUUUACAGGAAAGGCAGAGCCUGAAAUCUUGGGAAAGGGGGAUCCUGUGGCUCCUGGAAGGAUGGAUCCCAUGACUGUAAGAAAGGAAGAUCUUGGAUCCCUGGGAAAAGUAGAUCCUUUGUGCUCCAGCAAGACGUAUACAGUGUCACCGAGGAAGGAGGAUCCUGGGUCUUUGAGAAAGGUGGAUCCUGUGUCCUCAGACAAAGUGGACCCUGUAUUCCCAAGAAAGGAGGAGCCCAGGUAUUCAGGAAAAGAGCAUCCUGUGUCCUCAGAAAAGGUCGCUCCUACAUCUGCAGAAAAGGUAGAUCUUGUAUUGUCGGGAAAGAGAGAUCCUGGGCCCUCGGGAAAGGCAGAUCCCAUGCCCUUGGAAAGCAUGGAUUCUGCGUCCACAGGAAAGACAGAGCCGGGGCUCCUGGGCAAGCUGAUUCCAGGCUCAUCAGGCAAGAAUGGGCCUGUAUCCUCUGGGACCGGGGCUCCUGGGUCCUUGGGAAGGCUGGAUCCCACAUGCUUGGGGAUGGCAGAUCCCGCAUCUGUGGGAAAUGUAGAAACUGUGCCUGCCACAAAAGAGGACUCCCGGUUCCUGGGAAAGAUGGACCCUGCCUCCUCAGGAGAGGGGCGUCCUGUGUCUGGCCACACGGAUACUACGGCUUCAGCAAAGACAGAUCUCACAUCUUUGAAAAAUGUGGAUCCCAUGUCUUCAGGCAAGGUGGAUCCAGUUUCUCUGGGAAAGAUGGACCCCAUGUGCUCAGGAAAGCCAGAGCUCUUGUCUCCUGGACAGGCAGAGCGUGUGUCUGUGGGAAAGGCAGGAACUGUAUCCCCAGGAAAAGAGGACCCGGUGUCCUCCAGAAGGGAGGACCCCAUAUCUGCUGGAAGUAGAAAGACAUCAUCUGAAAAAGUGAAUCCUGAGUCUUCAGGAAAGACAAACCCUGUGUCUUCAGGUCCAGGCGAUCCCAGGUCCUUGGGGACAGCAGGUCCCCCAUCUGCAGUAAAGGCUGAGCCAGCGACGGGGGGAAAAGGAGAUCCCCUGUCCUCGGAGAAGGCAGGUCUGGUGGCCUCUGGAAAGGCGGCUCCCACAGCCUCAGGGAAGGCCGAGCCCCUCGCGGUGGGCAAGGAGGACCCUGUGAGCAAGGGAAAGGCAGACGCUGGCCCCUCUGGACAAGGGGACUCUGUGUCUAUAGGUAAAGUGGUCUCAACUCCAGGAAAAACAGUCCCGGUGCCCUCGGGGAAGGUGGAUCCCGUGUCCCUGGGAAAAGCAGAAGCUAUCCCAGAGGGAAAAGUGGGUUCUCUGCCUCUAGAGAAGGGGAGUCCUGUUACCACCACAAAGGCGGAUCCCAGGGCCUCGGGGAAAGCACAGCCGCAGUCUGGUGGCAAAGCAGAAACAAAGCUCCCUGGGCAAGAGGGCGCUGCAGCACCAGGGGAAGCAGGGGCUGUGUGUUUGAAAAAGGAGACACCACAGGCCUCAGAGAAGGUGGAUCCUGGAUCCUGCAGAAAAGCAGAGCCCCUUGCCUCAGGGAAGGGAGAGCCUGUGUCCCUGGGGAAAGCCGACUCUGCACCUUCCAGAAAAACGGAGUCCCCAUCCUUGGGGAAGGUGGUCCCCCUGAGUCUGGAGAAGACCAAGCCGUCCUCCUCCUCCAGGCAGUUAGACCGCAAAGCCCUCGGCUCAGCCCGGUCUCCCGAGGGUGCCAGGGGCAGUGAAGGCCGCGUGGAGCCGAAGGCCGAGCCCGUGUCCAGCACCGAGGCCUCCAGUCUCGGCCAGAAAGACCUGGAAGCCGCUGGGGCCGAGAGAAGCCCCUGCCCAGAGGCCGCAGCGCCCCCGCCGGGGCCGCGGACUCGCGACAACUUCACCAAGGCGCCGUCGUGGGAGGCGAGCGCCCCGCCGCCGCCGCGCGAGGACGCGGGCACUCAGGCGGGCGCGCAGGCCUGCGUCUCAGUGGCCGUGAGCCCCAUGUCUCCGCAGGACGGCGCUGGGGGCUCGGCCUUCAGCUUCCAGGCGGCGCCGCGCGCGCCCAGCCCGCCCUCGCGCCGAGAUGCGGGCCUGCAGGUGUCGCUGGGCGCCGCCGAGACGCGCUCCGUGGCCACUGGGCCCAUGACACCUCAAGCCGCCGCGCCGCCCGCCUUCCCCGAAGUGCGGGUGCGGCCCGGCUCAGCGCUGGCGGCCGCUGUAGCGCCCCCGGAGCCGGCUGAGCCCGUGCGAGACGUGAGCUGGGACGAGAAGGGCAUGACGUGGGAGGUAUACGGCGCCGCCAUGGAGGUGGAGGUGCUGGGCAUGGCCAUCCAGAAGCAUCUGGAGCGACAGAUCGAGGAGCACGGCCGCCAAGGGGCGCCCGCGCCGCCGCCCGCCGCCCGUGCCGGCCCCGGCCGUUCGGGCUCGGUGCGCACCGCGCCCCCAGAUGGCGCCGCCAAGCGUCCGCCCGGCCUGUUCCGCGCGCUGCUGCAGAGUGUGCGCCGGCCGCGGUGCUGCUCGCGGGCGGGACCCACGGCCGAGUGAUCUGCCCCCAUUUUGUACGCCCGAGUUUCCGACCUUCUCAGGCUCCCUUCUUGAUCACAGGCCCCUAGAAGGGGUCCCCUCUGCGUGCCACAGGCCUCCGAGGGGUUGUGCAGCCUCUAGGGCUGUUGCGUCCCCGUCUUUCCAGCCCCUCCCAUCACAAAUACAGAAGAACCCCUUCUACCAAGCUCCCUCGUGGCCACGAGGCCACGAACCCGGCCAGCCCUGACGCCCCACUGUCCCCUCACAGCCCUCAGCUCUACUCCCGGUCACACUGGGCGACCACGGGGGCCUGCUCAGCACCCUCACCUCCCACCCCCUGAGAGCUGGGGCAGGCUCCUGAGAUGUCUAGACUGGUGCGUUGUGGUCUCCGGUGGGGCCAGAUCCCCAGAACAGGGAGAGACUGCAUACAAGUCUGAGUGGCAGAAGCUUCAAGUGGGUGAGGAUCGGUGUGUGAGACCCGCGAGUGGGCACGUCUCUGAAUGUGAGGUCUCGGGCAGCACGUGAGGUAGAACGAGUGUGAGCGUCUCCACGCAGUGGCUGGCCCCGUGGCCGGGGCGUCUCUUGCAUGCUGUUGGUGGUCCUUCCCCAGUUCCUAUCUCCCACCCGCCUGGUUCCAGCCCCAUCCCCUCUCCCACUGAGUCACAGGUUUGAGAUUCCCAGAGAGGCCAAAGACAGCUACAGGAAGUACCCUGGGGGCUCAGCUGAGAGAGAGUCACAGAAAGGCCAGAGGGUCUCAGGAAGGUCUGGAGGUCACAGCUGGGCUCACAGAAGCUCUUGGGCCCUGGCAUCCUGGGUGACCGGUGUUCUUGGGUAUUGGGGACAGGACAGAGAGCUCAUUCUAUAACCACAGUUGUCUUUUAAAGGCCACCCUCUCCAGCCCCUUGUCCCCCCUGUGCUGUGAGCCCAAGUCCCUUGUGACCACUCAGUGUCCCGUCCCCACCCCUCCAGCCGCAGUUUUUGGCUACAAACUGUCACAGUAUACAUUGGUAAUAAAAUAUUUCCCCAA